GGCUCAGUGCUGCCGGGCACCGGGGCGGCGGGUUGGUCUACGCUGUGCGCGGCGGACGUCGGAGGCAGCGGGGAGCGGAGCGGGGCCGCCGGGGCCUCUCCAGGGCCGCAGCGGCAGCAGUUGGGCCCCCCGCCCCGGCCGGCGGACCGAAGAACGCAGGAAGGGGGCCGGGGGGACCCGCCCCCGGCCGGCCGCAGCCAUGAACUCCAACGUGGAGAACCUACCCCCGCACAUCAUCCGCCUGGUGUACAAGGAGGUGACGACACUGACCGCAGACCCACCCGAUGGCAUCAAGGUCUUUCCCAACGAGGAGGACCUCACCGACCUCCAGGUCACCAUCGAGGGCCCUGAGGGGACCCCAUAUGCUGGAGGUCUGUUCCGCAUGAAACUCCUGCUGGGGAAGGACUUCCCUGCCUCCCCACCCAAGGGCUACUUCCUGACCAAGAUCUUCCACCCGAACGUGGGCGCCAAUGGCGAGAUCUGCGUCAACGUGCUCAAGAGGGACUGGACGGCUGAGCUGGGCAUCCGACACGUACUGCUGACCAUCAAGUGCCUGCUGAUCCACCCUAACCCCGAGUCUGCACUCAACGAGGAGGCGGGCCGCCUGCUCUUGGAGAACUACGAGGAGUAUGCGGCUCGGGCCCGUCUGCUCACAGAGAUCCACGGGGGCGCCGGCGGGCCCAGCGGCAGGGCCGAAGCCGGUCGGGCCCUGGCCAGUGGCACUGAAGCUUCCUCCACCGACCCUGGGGCCCCAGGGGGCCCGGGAGGGGCUGAGGGUCCCAUGGCCAAGAAGCAUGCUGGCGAGCGCGAUAAGAAGCUGGCGGCCAAGAAAAAGACGGACAAGAAGCGGGCGCUGCGGCGGCUGUAGUGGGCUCUCUUCCUCCUUCCACCGUGACCCCAACCUCUCCUGUCCCCUCCCUCCAACUCUGUCUCUAAGUUAUUUAAAUUAUGGCUGGGGUCGGGGAGGGUACAGGGGGCACUGGGACCUGGAUUUGUUUUUCUAAAUAAAGUUGGAAAAGCAGCUUCUGUGUCUCACAGAUGCCCCAGGACCGCUGCAUGGUGCCAUGUGGCUCUGGGAGUUUGGCUCCCCUGCACAGGCCCUGGGUCCUUGUAAAGCCUCAUGGACUGCAGCAGUGGGUCCAUCUAGCUCACCAGCCUUGCUGUUUGAGGUUUGGGUCCACCUCUUUGUUCUGUGGAGGUAGAGCGGUCACAACCCCUCUUUGGAGUCAGAUUUCCAAUCUAAAAUGGGGCGAGGACCUGGAGCUGCUCCUGGUGGCCUGAGCGGCACUGCCCUAUACUUCUCCCUCUAGAAUAAUGGCCACGUUGGUGUGGCAGUGGUGUUCCUGCUCAGGACGGCCAGGUGCCAGCAGUCUGGCAUGAGGCUCGCCUCGUCUGUCUGGUUCUGGACUGGGCCAAGGUUCGGUCCCCUUGAAUCAUCUGAUCCUGCUUUGUGCUAAAGAUUGGUUUUUCCCUUGUGGGCAGCAAAGCCUGUUCCCACAUGUAUUUCUGCACAACAGAUCACAAAGCCAGCGGCUUAAAACAACACCCACUUCAGACUUUGUGUUGGAAGUCUGGACACGGCUGAGCUAGUCUCUGCUCAGUGCUUUGCAGGCUAAAAUUGAGGUAUUGGUUGUUGGUGUUCCUUAGUCUGGGUCCUCUUCCAUGCUCAUGGUUGUUGGCUGAUUUCAGUCCUCGUAGAACUAGGGUCUUAGCUCCAAGAAGCUGCCCCUCCUUGGGCCCUGGCAGGUCUGAUUUAAGGGCCCAUUCCCUUUGAGGUGCUCACCGGAUUAGGUCAGGCCCAUCCAGAUACUUAAGUGAUAAUGACUAAAUCACAGGGGUAAGAUCCCAGCUUAGUCUUAGUUUCUGCCCUCAAGGGGAAGGGAUUAACCUGGGUGUGCACACCAGGGGGUGGGGAAACUUCCCAUUCUAUUAAUGCGUUUAGGUUAUUUAGACCAAUGUCUCAUUAAUUUUAAAAAAAUUAAAAAUAGGCCAGGCGCAAUGGCUCACGCCUGUAAUCCCAACUUUAGGAGGUGAAAGGAUCACUUGAGGCCAGGAGUUAAAGACGAACGUGGGCAACACAGUGAGAUCCCAUCUCUACAAAAAGUAAAAUACAUUUACAAUAAAAAUCUACAAGUUCUGACCCAUAGGAGAGUGGAAAACUCAAAGGCUGCUUUUGUCCUGAAAGAAUUUGCCUAUUCUAAUAAAACAGCUGAGGUUGAAACGGCUCAGCCUCUGAAAGGGGUCUGACCCUUCCUUGAGCCCUUGCCUCCAGUGACAAUCUCCCAAGCUAAGGGAGAAAAGGAACCAAAAGUCUGCACUCCUCUCUACCUCUAGCAGUGCAGGGAGCGAAGGAAAGACAAGGGAAGAAACCCUUCAGAUUUUCAGAUCAAAUUCACAUCACUGGCCAUCCAAGAAAUCUUAAGCUCUGCGUUUAUCGUCAACCAUUUCUGCAUGAGGGAAGCAAACAGUCCUUGCUGAAGGAAGGUGCCUGCAUCCUGGGCCUCGGAACCCACUGAAAUAAUUUAGCGAAGUGCAUAAUAAAAAUAAUAUUUGCCCUUA